ACUUCCGGCGGCAGCGUCCGGGCUAGUUCCCGGCGCGAGCGGCCGCGGGCCAGUUUCUAUCUCCUCAUCCAGGGCUUGCGGGCGAGGCCUGUUUUAAGUCUCCAGUAACCGAGCGGAGGCCCGGCAGGCGCGACCCGGGCUGCGUACGUCAGAGCUGCCUCCGAAGUGGUAAAAUGUGCUGCGAGAAGUGGAGCCGCGUGGCGGAAAUGUUUCUCUUCAUUGAGGAGCGGGAGGAUUGUAAGAUACUGUGCCUUUGCUCCAGGGCAUUUGUGGAGGAUCGAAAAUUGUACAAUUUGGGAUUAAAAGGCUAUUACAUCAGAGACAGUGGCAACAAUUCAGGAGACCAGGCGACAGAAGAAGAGGAAGGUGGUUAUUCCUGUGGUACUGCAGAAUCACAUGACAGCAAAGGCAUAGGCCUGGAUGAAAGUGAACUUGAUUCUGAGGCUGAACUCAUGAGAAGUAUGGGAUUGCCACUUCAAUUUGGUAGGAUAACUGCACAUAAGGAUUUUGAGGUAUCUAUGAAUACUAGAAAUAAAGUUAAAAUAAAAAAGAAAAAACAUCAAAAGAAAUACUUAGAUGAAAUUGUGCAAGAAUCUUGGAGAAAAGAAUAUGAAGAAGACGACAUUUUGGCUUCAGAUGAUCCAUCUUCAAUUGAACAGUAUGAGAACACCAGAACAUAUGAACUUCAAAGCAAAAAAGAUACUGAGACAGAAAAUCCUCCAGUUGAAAACACAUUAUCUCCAAAGCUAGAAAUUACAGAGAAAUGGGAAAAGUAUUGGAAUGAAUAUGGAGGAGGACUAUUGUGGCAAAGUUGGCAAGAAAAACAUCCGGGUCAAGCACUAUCUUCUGAACCUUGGAACUUUCCUGAUACAAAGGAAGAAUGGGAGCAACAUUAUAGUCAACUUUAUUGGUAUUAUUUGGAACAAUUUCAGUAUUGGGAAGCUCAGGGUUGGACUUUUGAUGCCUCGCAAAGCUGUGAUACAGAUACUUACACAUCUAAAACAGAAGCUGAUGACAAGAACGAUGAAAAAUGCAUGAAAGUUGACUUAGUAUCUUUUCCAUCUUCACCUAUUAUGGUUGAUAAUGAUAGCUCUGGUACAAGUGAUAAGGAUCAUAGUGAAAUACUUGAUGGAAUUAGUAACAUAAAACUGAAUUCAGAGGAAGUAACACAGAGCCAAUUAGAUUCCUGUACAAGUCAUGAUGGUCAUCAACAGCUAAGUGAAGUUAGUAGCAAAAGAGAGUGCCCUGCUUCCGGCCAAAGUGAACCACGUAAUGGAGGAACCAAUGAGGAAAGCAACUCAUCGGGGAAUACAAACACAGACCCACCAGCUGAGGAUUCACAGAAGUCUUCAGGAGCAAACACAAGCAAAGACAGACCACAUGCCAGUGGUACUGAUGGAGAUGAAAGUGAGGAAGACCCACCUGAGCAUAAGCCAAGCAAACUGAAGAGGAGCCAUGAACUGGACAUUGAUGAAAACCCAGCUUCAGACUUUGAUGACAGUGGUUCCCUUCUAGGAUUCAAGUAUGGCUCAGGACAAAAAUAUGGUGGAAUCCCAAAUUUCAGUCAUCGGCAGGUCAGGUAUUUAGAGAAGAAUGUGAAGCUUAAGUCUAAGUACCUAGACAUGCGCAGACAAAUAAAGAUGAAAAACAAACACAUCUUCUUUACCAAAGAGUCAGAAAAACCAUUUUUCAAGAAAAGCAAAAUUCUGAGUAAGGUAGAAAAAUUCCUCACAUGGGUUAAUAAACCAAUGGAUGAAGAAGCAUCACAGGAAUCAUCUUCUCAUGACAAUGUGCACGACGCUUCCACAAGUAGUGAUUCAGAGGAACAAGACAUGUCUGUUAAAAAAGGUGAUGACCUACUGGAGACUAAUAAUCCAGAACCUGAAAAGUGUCAGAGCGUAUCUUCAGCUGGUGAACUUGAAACAGAAAACUAUGAAAGAGACAGCUUGCUAGCAACUGUUCCAGAUGAGCAGGAUUGUGUUACUCAAGAAGUGCCAGACUCCCGCCAGGCAGAAACUGAAGCUGAAGUGAAAAAGAAGAAGAACAAGAAGAAGAACAAAAAGGUGAAUGGUCUGCCUCCUGAAAUAGCUGCUGUUCCUGAGCUGGCAAAAUACUGGGCCCAGAGGUACAGGCUCUUCUCCCGUUUUGAUGAUGGGAUUAAGUUGGACAGAGAGGGCUGGUUUUCAGUUACACCCGAGAAGAUUGCUGAACACAUUGCUGGCCGUGUUAGUCAGUCCUUCAAGUGUGACGUUGUAGUAGACGCAUUCUGUGGAGUUGGAGGAAAUACCAUUCAGUUUGCCUUAACAGGAAUGAGAGUGAUUGCCAUUGAUAUCGAUCCUGUUAAGAUUGCCCUUGCUCGCAAUAAUGCAGAAGUUUAUGGGAUAGCAGAUAAGAUAGAGUUCAUCUGUGGAGAUUUCUUGCUGCUGGCUUCUUUUUUAAAGGCUGAUGUUGUGUUCCUCAGCCCACCUUGGGGAGGGCCAGACUAUGCCACUGCAGAGACCUUUGACAUUAGAACAAUGAUGUCUCCUGAUGGCUUUGAAAUUUUCAGACUUUCUAAGAAGAUCACUAAUAAUAUUGUUUAUUUUCUUCCAAGAAAUGCUGAUAUUGACCAGGUGGCAUCCUUAGCUGGGCCUGGAGGGCAAGUGGAAAUAGAACAGAACUUCCUUAACAACAAAUUGAAGACAAUCACUGCAUAUUUUGGUGACCUAAUUCGAAGACCAGCCUCUGAAACCUAACUAUGCAGCAGUGCGAGGACAAAAGAUCAUGGAGUGGUCAAAAUAUUCAGAUGAGACAUUUGGCAUGUCUUCCUUUAUUCACUGAUAUUUUCUACCCAUGGUCUUAUAUCACCGUAUGAAAUGGAAACUUACAGGACUUAAAUAUCAGUGAAAUAUUUUGAGAUCUUUGAAUAAUUCCUUUAGAGGAAUUAUACAAAAUUAAUAUAUAUGAGUCCUUUGUAAUUUAUUUUUUUUUGAGACAGGAUCUCACUUUUACCGCCCAGGCUGGAGUGCAGUGCCAUGAUCACAGCUCACUGCAGGUUCAGCCUUCUGAGUUCAAGCAAUCCUUCUGUCUCAGUCUCCUCAGUAGCUGGGGCUUUAGGUGGGCACUGCCACACCGUACUAAUUUUUGUAUUUUUUGUAGAGACGAGGUCCCACCAUGUUGCCCAGGCUGGUGUCAAACUCCUGGGCUCAGUCAGUCCCCCCAUCUCACCCUCCCCAAGUGCUGGAAUUACAGGCGUGAGCUACUGUGCCCAGCCUUACGGACAUCCUUUUGAAUUAUCUUUUUCACUCAUAGAAUAUGAAUACAUUUAUUUAGACUUUUUCUAGAACUUUCCUGUUUUCAUGUCUUUGCUUCAUCUGGAAUUGGCUUAACACCCUUUUAUAAAGUUUGUGUUUGUAAAAUUUCCAUUGUGACAUCAAUACGCAAUAUAUUUUGUAAUAUAGGAGUUUCUAUUUUUUUAUUAAAAUGGCAAUGAAAGCAAGAGGGAUAUGUGUUGCUUAAUUAUUCAUCUAAAAAGUUUGUUCAGUCAUUUUUACAAGUAGGCAAAAAAAUAGUGACAUACAACACUUGUCCAUUGAAGGUUAGACCUGGGACUUCUAUAUUUUAAUAAUAUGAGCGUGUUAAACAUUAAACAGAACAUGAUACUGGCUGGGAUAAGAUUAGAGAAUUGAAACAAAUUUGGGGAAUUUCCAAUAAAUACUAGAAAAUUAGACUAGAAAAAUAGCUGUUAUAUAAAUAACUUUGUUGGAAUAUGCUAAUUUUAGUGUCUUGAAAGUUUACAAUUUAUCUGAUUGCUCUGCAGUACAGUAGCAACUGAGCUGAUCAAUAAAGGUGAAAUUACUUUUUCAUUAAUUCGCAAUUUCAAAAUCUGUCCAAAUGUUCUUGGUUUUUAAACUUUAUGUAGCAUUCUUUUUUUUUUUUUUAGACAGAGUCUUGCUCUGUCGCCCAGGCUGGAGUGCAAUGGCGUGAUCUCAGCUUACUGCAACCUCCACCUCCUACCUCAGCCUCCCGAGUAGCUGGGACUACAGGCACCUGCCACCACAUCCAGCUAAUUUUUUAUAUUUUUAGUAGCUAUGGGGUUUCACCGUGUUAGCCAGGAUGGUCUCGAUCUCCUGACCUUGUGAUCCAACCACCUCAGCCUCCCGUAGUUCUGGGAUUACAGGCGUGAGCCACCGCGCCUGGCUUUAUGUAGCAUUCUUAAAGUCACUAGGGAGAUGGCAGGUGAAGUAAAGGCAGAUUUCCAAAAUCACUAAUUUUUUUUAGUUUUUUGUCACUUAACCUUUCUUGCAUAUACUUCUUUCCACAGCUCAUUUUCUUACUUGUAUAUUAAUAAAGCUAACUCAUCUUCCUGAAUAUACAUGAUUUUACAUGAGAAGAGCAGGAAGCUUAGGCUUGGUUAGCUAAAACUAAGAUAUUGCUGCCCACUAAUCACACAGGGAUAAAACUAAUAGACUGUUAAGAUUGUCAGUACUCAAUAGGA